AUGUGUUCUUUUUUCUUGUGCCAAACAGGUAAACAGGCAAAAAUAUCAAUGGGAGAAGAAAACCAAACCUUUGUGUCCAAGUUUAUCUUCCUGGGUCUUUCACAGGACUUGCAGACCCAGAUCCUGCUAUUUAUCCUUUUCCUCAUCAUUUAUCUGCUGACCGUGCUUGGAAACCAGCUCAUCAUCAUUCUCAUCUUCCUGGAUUCUCGCCUUCACACUCCCAUGUAUUUUUUUCUUAGAAAUCUCUCCUUUGCAGAUCUCUGUUUCUCUACUAGCAUUGUCCCUCAAGUGUUGGUUCACUUCUUGGUAAAGAGGAAAACCAUUUCUUUUUAUGGGUGUAUGACACAGAUAAUUGUCUUUCUUCUGGUUGGGUGUACAGAGUGUGCGCUGCUGGCAGUGAUGUCCUAUGACCGGUAUGUGGCUGUCUGCAAGCCCCUGUACUACUCUACCAUCAUGACACAACGGGUGUGUCUCUGGCUGUCCUUCAGGUCCUGGGCCAGUGGGGCACUAGUGUCUUUAGUAGAUACCAGCUUUACUUUCCAUCUUCCCUACUGGGGACAGAAUAUAAUCAAUCACUACUUUUGUGAACCUCCUGCCCUCCUGAAGCUGGCUUCCAUAGACACUUACAGCACAGAAAUGGCCAUCUUUUCAAUGGGCGUGGUAAUCCUCCUGGCCCCUGUCUCCCUGAUUCUUGGUUCUUAUUGGAAUAUUAUCUCCACUGUUAUCCAGAUGCAGUCUGGGGAAGGGAGACUCAAGGCUUUUUCCACCUGUGGCUCCCAUCUUAUUGUUGUUGUCCUCUUCUAUGGGUCAGGAAUAUUCACCUACAUGCGACCAAACUCCAAGACUACAAAAGAACUGGAUAAAAUGAUAUCUGUGUUCUAUACAGCGGUGACUCCAAUGUUGAACCCCAUAAUUUAUAGCUUGAGGAACAAAGAUGUCAAAGGGGCUCUCAGGAAACUAGUUGGGAGAAAGUGCUUCUCUCAUAGGCAGUGA